GGAGUAACAGUGGGGCGUUUGAGAGGAUGGAGGGUUGAAUGCCAAAACUUCGUAAUCGUAGAAAAUUCUGGAAAGCCGCCGGCGGGGCAAGGCCACGAGGAUCCUCCUCGCAGCACCGCGCCGCGCGGGGCCCAGGGGCCGCGCUCACGCCCGCCGCUCGGCGCAGACACGAGUGCCCCCGACUUGAGCCGAACCUCUAGCCGAUGCCGGCGCCGCCGCCGCCGGGGAUGCGUAAGCCGACUGGGAAGCGAGGGGGGGAGGCGGCCUGCGCGGCACCGCCCGACCUGGCCGCGGCGGGCUGAGCCCCAGGUUCCGGAGGAAUGCUCGCUCCCCGCUGGAGUCCUACCAGCCCAACACGGACCUGAGCCGCGACCACGCGGGCUGCAGCCUGCAGCACAUCAGCUACCCGGAGAACGCGGACGCGGAAGCACCGCUGCUCAGCACCCCCGAAGAAACACGGAAUCCAGAGAGGCACAGGCACCGCCCCGGCGCGCACAGCUGCACUCAGCGGCUUCCUUCCUACUACAUACAUACAUAGGAGUGGGAGCCGAGGACCACUUGUUGCUUGCGGACUUCCUCUAGCAUAAAAGAUGGAAAGAAAACACACACCGAAGCAAGGGACCAAAGGAACAGAAAAGAAACGCAGAGAUCAUAGGAAAACUGCAAAGAAAUACUUGAUAAUAUCUUCCAAACGAUUAGAGAAGACAUAACAUUCAUUAAGAAUACACAUAUAGAUGUAUAUAUACGUAUGAAGAAAACCUGCUUGAUAUCACACAGUCAGGAGUCAACUGAGUUGGGGCUUUGAACUUAGGUUUAUCUGAUGCCAAAGUUUGUGAUGCUCUUCAACCAUUUAGGGUACCGCAGAGUGUGGAUUUUGAAUCACCUGCAUCAGCAUCAUUUUAAAAUAUAGAUUCUGUGGUCCUGACCAGGUCUCUGAAGUCAGAAUAUGAAGUGGAGCUAGGAAUCUAACUUCUUAACAAGUUCCCUAGAUGCCUAAGGGUAUCCCUGAAUGAUACAGUUUUGUUUGAAAGACUGAAAAGCCCAAAGCUGGCCCUUUUGGGAAAUAGCAGUAAAUCAUUGAUAUGUGAAGGUUCCCAGCAGGAGGAUGAAAAUUUACAGGAAUUCGGAGGAAAAUAUUUCAGUGGUCAUUACUAAAACGCUCAGAGUCAGAUACAUUCAGCAUCAUACCGUAAGUCCCGUUAGUCAAAGCAUAAACAAGCGCAGGGCCUGGCAUGGCUUCCUUCAAGUUGGCUGACUCAGUCUGGGAGGAUUCACUCAGCAAGAGGCAGAGGAACCAAGGCAGGAUGAAGACAUUGCCUGUGCUCGUGCUGUCUCUUACCUUACUGACUGUCUUCUCAGAGACCUCCCCGAUUUUGACAGAGAAGCAGGCCAAACAGCUCCUAAGAUCUCGGCGACAGGAUAGACCAAGCAAACCCGGAUUCCCCGAUGAGCCAAUGCGGGAAUACAUGCACCACCUGCUCGCCCUGGAGCAUCGCGCUGAGGAGCAGUUCCUGGAGCACUGGCUGAACCCUCACUGCAAACCCCACUGUGACAGGAACAGGAUUCAUCCUGUGUAAGGGGAUCAGGACCAGCCUCGCAAGCAUUUUAAUAGACAACAAGCUGGAUAAUGUCGAAGCAAGACAAGGCUGCUUCUUUCACUUGUUUUUAAAUUGCAGAAAUGGAUGUCUUCAGACCUCGUGAACUGUGGGCAUAUCAAAGAUUGCCUUGGAAAUGGCAAAUAUAUAUACUGCUUCAUUUUACUAACCUGCAUAGAUCACUAAAACCAAUAGCUUAAAGCAUAGACACCUCCCAAAGGUCUUCCCAUCAGUUUGCAAGAGUGGGAACAACCAGAAUCUUACCUGGGGUUGAUGGAGCUGGAACUCCCAGACCAGGAGUUGGGGCAGGCUGCCUGCCCUAAGGAAUUUGGGGAAUCCUUGUUCAGAGUAGUGAAGCAUACCACUUGGGGUUGCUGAGUUGUUUUGUCCUCUAUUUUUUUCCUCUUCUUUUCUGCCCUAAUAAACAUUGGUAUUAAAUUUA